AGUUUAAUAGUAGCGCGGUCCCCAUACGGCUGUAAUCAGUGAAUUAGAAAAAAAACACCCUAGCAGCGAUAUUCUAUGAUAGAUUUUUUUUCCUCUGCGCUCGCCUUUUUCCUAGGCCUUGCCCCCCCAAAGCCCCUCCAAAAGAGGGAACUUUUUCUCUGAGGGGGCUCCAAGGAGAAGGCCAUGAAUUACGAAUUUGAGCGAGAGAUUGGUUUUAUCAAUAGCCAGCCGUCGCUCGCUGAGUGCCUGACAUCUUUUCCCCCUGUCGCUGAUACAUUUCAAAGUUCAUCAAUCAAGACCUCGACGCUUUCACACUCGACACUGAUUCCUCCUCCUUUUGAGCAGACCAUUCCCAGCCUGAACCCCGGCAGUCACCCUCGCCACGGCGCUGGCGGCCGCCCCAAGCCGAGCCCCGCGGGCAGCCGCGGCAGCCCGGUGCCCGCCGGCGCCCUGCAGCCGCCCGAGUACCCCUGGAUGAAGGAGAAGAAGGCGGCCAAGAAAACCGCACUUCUGCCGGCCGCCGCCGCCGCCGCCACCGCCGCAGCCACCGGCCCUGCUUGCCUCAGCCACAAAGAAUCCCUGGAAAUCGCCGAUGGCAGCGGCGGGGGAUCGCGGCGCCUGAGAACUGCUUACACCAACACACAGCUUCUAGAGCUGGAAAAAGAAUUUCAUUUCAACAAGUACCUUUGCAGACCCCGAAGGGUGGAGAUUGCAGCGCUGCUGGAUUUGACUGAGAGACAAGUGAAAGUGUGGUUUCAGAACCGGAGGAUGAAGCACAAGAGGCAGACCCAGUGCAAGGAAAACCAAAACAGCGAAGGGAAAUGUAAAAGCCUUGAGGACUCCGAGAAAGUAGAGGAGGACGAGGAAGAGAAGACGCUCUUUGAGCAAGCCCUUAGCGUCUCUGGGGCCCUUCUGGAGAGGGAAGGCUACACUUUUCAGCAAAAUGCCCUCUCUCAGCAGCAGGCUCCCAAUGGACACAAUGGCGACUCCCAAAGUUUCCCAGUCUCGCCUUUAACCAGCAAUGAGAAAAAUCUGAAACAUUUUCAGCACCAGUCACCCACUGUUCCCAACUGCUUGUCAACAAUGGGCCAGAACUGUGGAGCUGGCCUAAACAAUGACAGUCCUGAGGCCCUUGAGGUCCCCUCUUUGCAGGACUUUAGCGUUUUCUCCACAGAUUCCUGCCUGCAGCUUUCAGAUGCAGUUUCACCCAGUUUGCCAGGUUCCCUCGACAGUCCCGUAGAUAUUUCAGCUGACAGCUUAGACUUUUUUACAGACACACUCACCACAAUCGACUUGCAGCAUCUGAAUUACUAAAAACAUUAAAGCAAAACAAAGCAUCACCAAACAAAAACUCCUUUGACCAGGUGGUUUUGCCUUCUUUUAUUUGGGAGUUUAUUUUUUAUUUUCUUCUUGACCUACCCCUUCCCUCCUUUAAGUGUUGAGGAUUUUCUGUUUAGUGAUUCCCUGACCCAGUUUCAAACAGAGCCAUCUUUUACAGAUUAUUUUGGAGUUUUAGUUGUUUUAAACCUAACUCAACAACCCUUUAUGUGAUUCCUGAGAGCAGUAUGAGGCCUGCAAGAAAGUGAUCAUAUAAUUGUAUCUUCACUUUCUUUUUAUUUUUGUAUUACAUUGGGAUGCAUUGUCAUGCAUAUUUUUUGUAGAAUAAAUUCUCCUUUGCUAUAAGUA